CUAGUCCUGAGAGGCUGGGCCGGCGGCGGCUGCGGCGGGAGACCGGUGACCCGCGGCUGGGCGCCUCGGCCAUGACUGCGGAGCUGCAGCAGGACGACGCGGCCGGCGCGGCAGACGGCCACGGCUCGAUUUUUAAGGAGGGGGAGGAGCUGCGUGAUGAAUAGAAAGUCUACUGAUGAUGAUCUCCUGUUCCCAAUGUCUAAGAAGAUUGAAAUCAAUAUAAGGACUUCUGAUCUAAGAAUCUGGUGAGAGUGAAAGAACCCUGGUUUGAGAGAAAAGCUAAUGUCUGUAUGAAGAAACUUGGGAAGAGGGCAAUUUGAGCAUGUCUUCUAGUGUUACUUCGGAAUGUUAUAACUUAACACCACCUCCUCACCCCUCAAGUACUGCACUUUUUCAAGAGAAAACGGGAAAUCUGUGCCAGUUGUUCAAAUACGAGUUUGGAGAUGAGAAACUAUAUUUGUCGUACAAAGCUGGCAGACAGAUACCCUCAGAGCUGCCAAAUGCUGUUAAAUCAACUGAGAGAAAUCACAGGCAUUCAGGACCCUUCCUUUCUCCAUGAAGCUCUGAAGGCCAGUAAUGGUGACAUUACUCAGGCAGUCAGCCUUCUCACUGAUGAGAGAGUUAAGGAGCCCAGUCAAGACACUGUUGCUACAGAACCAUCUGAAGUAGAGGGGAGUGCUGCCAACAAGGAAGUAUUAGCAAAAGUUAUAGACCUUACUCAUGAUAACAAAGAUGAUCUUCAGGCUGCCAUUGCUUUGAGUCUACUGGAGUCUCCCAAAAUUCAAGCUGAUGGAAGAGAUCUUAACAGGAUGCAUGAAGCAACCUCUGCAGAAACUAAACGCUCAAAGAGAAAACGCUGUGAAGUCUGGGGAGAAAACCCCAAUCCCAAUGACUGGAGGAGAGUUGAUGGUUGGCCAGUUGGGCUGAAAAAUGUUGGCAAUACAUGUUGGUUUAGUGCUGUUAUUCAGUCUCUCUUUCAAUUGCCUGAAUUUCGAAGACUUGUUCUCAGUUAUAGUCUGCCACAAAAUGUACUUGAAAAUUGUCGAAGUCAUACAGAAAAGAGAAAUAUCAUGUUUAUGCAAGAGCUUCAGUAUUUGUUUGCUCUAAUGAUGGGAUCAAAUAGAAAAUUUGUAGACCCGUCUGCAGCCCUGGAUCUAUUAAAGGGAGCAUUCCGAUCAUCUGAGGAACAGCAGCAAGAUGUGAGUGAAUUCACACACAAGCUCCUGGAUUGGCUAGAGGACGCAUUCCAGCUAGCUGUUAAUGUUAACAGUCCCAGGAACAAAUCUGAAAAUCCAAUGGUGCAGCUGUUCUAUGGUACUUUCCUGACUGAAGGGGUUCGUGAAGGAAAACCCUUUUGUAACAAUGAGACCUUCGGCCAGUAUCCUCUUCAGGUAAACGGUUAUCGCAACUUAGACGAGUGUUUGGAAGGGGCCAUGGUGGAGGGUGAUGUUGAGCUUCUUCCCUCCGAUCACUCGGUGAAGUAUGGACAAGAGCCUACCUGUACCUGAGUAGGGAGAACCCACUGCCUCCAUAUUUUCGGAGGGUAAAAGUACAGUGAUUAACUCCUAUGCGUUGGUUUACAAAGCUACCUCCAGUGUUGACCUUUGAACUCUCAAGAUUUGAGUUUAAUCAGUCCCUUGGGCAGCCAGAGAAAAUUCACAAUAAGCUGGAAUUUCCUCAGAUUAUUUAUAUGGACAGGUACAUGUACAGGAGCAAGGAGCUUAUUCGAAAUAAGAGAGAGUGUAUUCGAAAGUUGAAGGAGGAAAUAAAAAUUCUGCAGCAAAAAUUGGAAAGGUAUGUGAAAUAUGGCUCAGGCCCAGCUCGGUUCCCGCUCCCGGACAUGCUGAAAUAUGUUAUUGAAUUUGCUAGUACAAAACCUGCCUCAGAAAGCUGUCCACCUGAAAGUGACACACAUAUGACAUUACCACUUUCUUCAGUGCACUGCUCGGUUUCUGACCAGACAUCCAAGGAAAGUACAAGUACAGAAAGCUCUUCUCAGGAUGUUGAAAGUACCUUUUCUUCUCCUGAAGAUUCUUUACCCAAGUCUAAACCACUGACAUCUUCUCGGUCUUCCAUGGAAAUGCCUUCACAGCCAGCUCCACGAACAGUCACAGAUGAGGAGAUAAAUUUUGUUAAGACCUGUCUUCAGAGAUGGAGGAGUGAGAUUGAACAAGAUAUACAAGAUUUAAAGACUUGUAUUGCAAGUACUACUCAGACUAUUGAACAGAUGUACUGCGAUCCUCUCCUUCGUCAGGUGCCUUAUCGCUUGCAUGCAGUUCUUGUUCAUGAAGGACAAGCAAAUGCUGGACACUAUUGGGCCUAUAUCUAUAAUCAACCCCGACAGAGCUGGCUCAAGUACAAUGACAUCUCUGUUACUGAAUCUUCCUGGGAAGAAGUUGAAAGAGAUUCCUAUGGAGGCCUGAGAAAUGUUAGUGCUUACUGUCUGAUGUACAUUAAUGACAAACUACCCUACUUCAAUGCAGAGGCAGCCCCAACUGAAUCAGAUCAAAUGUCAGAAGUGGAAGCCCUAUCUGUGGAACUCAAGCAUUACAUUCAGGAGGAUAACUGGCGGUUUGAGCAGGAAGUAGAGGAGUGGGAAGAAGAGCAGUCUUGCAAAAUCCCUCAAAUGGAGUCCUCCACCAACUCCUCAUCACAGGACUACUCUACAUCACAAGAGCCUUCAGUAGCCUCUUCUCAUGGGGUUCGCUGCUUGUCGUCUGAGCAUGCUGUGAUUGUAAAGGAGCAAACUGCCCAGGCUAUUGCAAACACAGCCCGUGCCUAUGAGAAGAGCGGUGUAGAAGCGGCACUGAGUGAGGUGAUGCUGAGCCCUGCCAUGCAAGGGGUCAUCCUGGCCAUAGCUAAAGCCCGUCAGACCUUUGACCGAGAUGGGUCUGAAGCAGGGCUGAUUAAGGCAUUCCAUGAAGAAUACUCCAGGCUCUAUCAGCUUGCCAAAGAGACCCCCACCUCUCACAGUGAUCCUCGACUUCAGCAUGUCCUUGUCUACUUUUUCCAAAAUGAAGCACCCAAAAGGGUAGUAGAACGAACCCUUCUGGAACAGUUUGCAGAUAAAAAUCUUAGCUAUGAUGAAAGAUCAAUCAGCAUUAUGAAGGUGGCUCAAGCGAAACUGAAGGAAAUUGGUCCAGAUGACAUGAAUAUGGAAGAGUACAAGAAGUGGCAUGAAGAUUAUAGUUUGUUCCGAAAAGUGUCUGUGUAUCUCCUAACAGGCCUAGAACUCUAUCAAAAAGGAAAGUACCAAGAGGCACUUUCCUACCUGGUAUAUGCCUACCAGAGCAAUGCUGCCCUGCUGAUGAAGGGGCCCCGCCGGGGGGUCAAAGAAUCCGUGAUUGCUUUAUACCGAAGAAAAUGCCUUCUGGAGCUGAAUGCCAAAGCAGCUUCUCUUUUUGAAACAAAUGAUGAUCACUCCGUAACUGAGGGCAUUAAUGUGAUGAAUGAACUGAUCAUCCCCUGCAUUCACCUUAUCAUUAAUAAUGACAUUUCCAAGGAUGAUCUGGAUGCCAUUGAGGUCAUGAGAAACCAUUGGUGCUCUUACCUUGGGCAAGAUAUUGCAGAAAAUCUGCAGCUGUGCCUAGGGGAGUUUCUACCCAGACUUCUAGAUCCUUCUGCAGAAAUCAUCGUCUUGAAAGAGCCUCCAACUAUUCGACCCAAUUCUCCCUAUGACCUAUGUAGCCGAUUUGCAGCUGUCAUGGAGUCAAUUCAGGGAGUUUCAACUGUGACAGUGAAAUAAGCUCCCACAUGUUCAAGGCCCAUUCUGGUUCCUGGCUGCCUGCCUCUUGCACAGAAGUUCGUUGUCAUAGUGCUCACCUUGGGAAAAGGAUUAGGUGGGCACAUAAGAUUCCGAUCAGACCCCAACCAUGCUGCAUGUGUAAAGAAGGAUUGAAAAUAAAAUUGCACUUUUUAGGUACAAAAUCAUAAAAGCUGUUUCACUAGAAAAGGCAGAAAGCAGUGUAUUAAGGUGUUGAAUUACGCCAGAAGACCUGAAAUGCCUUGUACCUACAACAAUGCUUAGGCUUUUCUAAGCCUCUUGCCACUUUUAAAAUUAUCCUUCAGGCAUAAAUAUUUUUGACAGCAGAAUAGAAGAAUGAUUCAUGAGAACCUGAACCAGAUGAACAGCUACUAGUUAUUUUAUCAAAUACAGAUGACAUUUAAAAAUUCUUAACUACAAGAGAUUAGAAAUAUAAACCUUGCCUGGCUCUUGCCAGGAGAUAACAAAAUGGGUUGCUGAUGAACUGCACCCUUUUACAUGUGGGUAGAAUAUAAGCUCACAUGGCAGUGAGAUGUUGAAAAGUCAAAAGAGACCUGUCUCUCUCCUUUCUUUUCUAUCUUUAAACCAGAAAACCUCAUACUCAGUCCUCAGUGAAAGAAAGUAAAGUAUUAAGGACUUUAGACAGAAGAGCAUUGUGUAACUUGACUGAAGAUCAUCCAUUAAUAGUUAUUAGGCAUUUAGGUAAAAUUUUCUAAUACCUAAAAAUUGUCAAAAACAGUCAAUAGGGCUACUGCUGGCCCAAAGACCAUUUAGGUCCACCUCCUCUUUUUUGCUCUUUUUUUUUUUCUGUGACAGUUUCACUGUGUCGCCCAGGCUGGCGUUCAGUGGUGCAAUCUCAGCUCACUGCAAACUCUGUCUCCUGGGCUCAAGUGAUUCUCGUGCCUCAGCCUCCCGAAUAGCUGGAAUUACGGGCAUGCACCACCACACCUGGCUAAUUUUUGUAUUUUUAAUAGAGAUGGGGUUUCACCAUAUUGGCCAGGCUGAUCUCUAACUCCUGGCCUCAAGUGAUCUAUCUGCCUCCCUCAGCCUCCCAAAGUCUGGGAUUGCAGACAAGUCAUCGUACCCGGCCUUCUUUUUUGCCCUUAAAAGUAAGGGAUGUGGGUUUGUACAAAAAAAAAAAAAAAAAAAAAAAAACCAGCAUACAUAUGCAAAACUAUAUAUAUAUGUAUAUGUAGAGAAAAAUACUUCCCAUUGAUCAUUUUUAAAAGGCUUCUGAUUGGAUAUUGUGUUUUAACCAAAUUUUAAAGAUUAAUGGAAUCAUGAAAGGGAAAAAAAUUGAUACAACUAUGCAGAUUUUAUAAAUGUGCAAUAAAAGUAUUUGUUUUA